GCGCCUCCGCUCGCCUGUGGCUGCGUCGCGCGCUCUUCCUCGGAGCUACCCAGGCGGCUGGUGUGCAGCAAGCUCCGCGCCGACCCCUGACGCCUGACGCCUGUCCCCGGCCCGGCAUGAGCCGCUACCUGCUGCCGCUGUCGGCGCUGGGCACGGUAGCAGGCGCCGCCGUGCUGCUCAAGGACUAUGUCACCGGUGGGGCUUGCCCCAGCAAGGCCACCAUCCCUGGGAAGACGGUCAUCGUGACGGGUGCCAACACAGGCAUCGGGAAGCAGACCGCCUUGGAACUGGCCAGGAGAGGAGGCAACAUCAUCCUGGCCUGCCGAGACAUGGAGAAGUGUGAGGCGGCAGCAAAGGACAUCCGCGGGGAGACCCUCAAUCACCAUGUCAACGCCCGGCACCUGGACUUGGCUUCCCUCAAGUCUAUCCGAGAGUUUGCAGCAAAGAUCAUUGAAGAGGAGGAGCGAGUGGACAUUCUAAUCAACAACGCGGGUGUGAUGCGGUGCCCCCACUGGACCACCGAGGACGGCUUCGAGAUGCAGUUUGGCGUUAACCACCUGGGUCACUUUCUCUUGACAAACUUGCUGCUGGACAAGCUGAAAGCCUCAGCCCCUUCGCGGAUCAUCAACCUCUCGUCCCUGGCCCAUGUUGCUGGGCACAUAGACUUUGACGACUUGAACUGGCAGACGAGGAAGUAUAACACCAAAGCCGCCUACUGCCAGAGCAAGCUCGCCAUCGUCCUCUUCACCAAGGAGCUGAGCCGGCGGCUGCAAGGCUCUGGUGUGACUGUCAACGCCCUGCACCCCGGCGUGGCCAGGACAGAGCUGGGCAGACACACGGGCAUCCAUGGCUCCACCUUCUCCAGCACCACACUCGGGCCCAUCUUCUGGCUGCUGGUCAAGAGCCCCGAGCUGGCCGCCCAGCCCAGCACAUACCUGGCCGUGGCGGAGGAACUGGCGGAUGUUUCCGGAAAGUACUUCGAUGGACUCAAACAGAAGGCCCCGGCCCCCGAGGCUGAGGAUGAGGAGGUGGCCCGGAGGCUUUGGGCUGAAAGUGCCCGCCUGGUGGGCUUAGAGGCUCCCUCUGUGAGGGAGCAGCCCCUCCCCAGAUAACCUCUGGAGCAGAUUUGAAAGCCAGGAUGGCGCCUCCAGACCGAGGACAGCUGUCCGCCAUGCCCGCAGCUUCCUGGCACUACCUGAGCCGGGAGACCCAGGACUGGCGGCCGCCAUGCCCGCAGUAGGUUCUAGGGGGCGGUGCUGGCCGCAGUGGACUGGCCUGCAGCCAGCAAACCCCAAACAGGAACCUAUGGUUGGUGAUGGAUGUGCGUUCAGAAAGCAGGGAGGGAGGGGGAGUCAGAGGUGAGGGGGUCAUCAGCCAUAGCUGUCCGCUGCAUCACCCCCUCGCUAUCUCCAGGAAGCGUUCUGGGCUUUUCCUGUUGUGCAGUGUGGAAGUGCUCUAUCUUCAUUCAUAUCAAGGAAAGUCAAAGGACAAACUAAAGCCGGCAGCGUCUUUCUGGCUUCCUAGUCAGGCUGUUCGGUAGCGGAGUGUCACCCUGAUUUCCAGCCCCGCAGCACACACAGUGAGAGCCUGCCUGGCGUGAUUCAGAGGCAACGUAUUUCCCAAGGUGGCUGUGAAGGAACCAGGGGGAUAAACACAGCCCGUGAACCGCACGCCAGAGGACAGGUCCGGCUGCCUGCCGCGGAGUCGUCACGGCGUGUCGCGUCUGAGCGCUUCUCCAAAGCACCCAAGUGGCACCCGGGGUGACAGUUACAUCAUCUUGAGUACAGUUCUCUCAAGGAAAAAGCAAGCCCAGCAUCUUCUGCCAUGGCAACCCUGGCUUGGAGCCUCCAUAAGAGAGAAGGCCCUAAGAAUAAUACCAUUUUCUUGCUCUAAGUUGCUCUUACGGGAAAGAAGUGAUAAUAUUCUUCCUAAACGCCAUCAUUCGUGCAUCCUUCCCACCUAUAUGUGUCACCGGAUCAUUCUCCGCCUGGGCGGGGCCGUCCUGUGCACUGCAGAAUGCUGAGCAGUGUCCUUGGCUUCGACCGACCACAUGCCAGGAGCACCCCAAUUUCUGCCAUCGGGUGAUUGACUUCACUGUUGCAUUUGAUUUUUUAUGUAUCUUUUAAAAGGACCCAAUAGGGCCAGGCACAGUGGCUCACACUUGUAAUCCCAGCACUUUGGGAGGCUGAGGUCGGUGGAUUGCUUGAGCCCAGGAGGAGUUCAAGACCAGCCUGGGCAACAUAGUGAAACCCCAACUCUACAAAAAACAAAUGUUUUAUUUUUAUUUAUUUUAGAUGGAGUUUCACUCUUGUUGCCCAGGCUGGAGUGCAGUGGCGCAAUCUCGGCUCACUGCAACUUCUGCCUCCCGGGUUCAAGCGAUUCUCCUGCCUCAGCCUCCUGAGUAUCUGGGAUUACAGGCAUGCGCCACCACACCCAGCUAAUUUUGUAUUUUUAGUAGAGAUGGCGUUUCUCCAUGUUGGUCAGGCUGGUCUCAAACUCCCGACCUCAGGUGAUCUGCCUGCCUCGGCCUCCCAGAGUGUUGGGAUUACAGGCGUGAGCCACCACGCCCAGCCGGGUUUAUAGUUUUAUAACCCUUAUGACAAAUCUCAUAGUAUUCUGCAGGGAUAAGCAUGAAACCACUCGUUCAAUAAGUGCAAACAAAAACGCCAACAAUUCUUAAGACAUUUCUAAUCUUAUUUUACCAAUAAUUUUAAAGCCAGCUUAUGUAUUAAAGAUUUAUAACUACUUUUAUUAACACGUUUAAAAUUCUAUGCAGCUUAAAGCAUUUAUAAUGGAUAAAACUGCCAAUACUGAGUGCCUGACAUAAUAUUUGAAAGGUGGCAGGCAUUCAACCAUGGUCACUGAAUGAGAGAUGUAGGGAAGAUGAUGGCAGGGAGGUUUUUAGAUAUCAACACCCUGAUAGUUCUCAUUUUAACCACCUGUAAGUGCACAUACAAGUCAACGGCACUGGCCGGGCGCGGUGGCUCAUGCCUGUAUUCCCAGCACUUUGGGAGGCCAAAUCACAAGGUCAGGAGAUCGAGACCAUCCUGGCUAACACGGUGAAACCCCGUCUCUACUAAAAAUACAAAAAAUCAACUAGGCAUGGUGGCACGCACCUGUAGUCCCAGCUACUCAGGAGGCUGAGGCAGGAGAAUCGCUUGAACCUGGGAGGCGGAGGUUGCGGUGAGCCAAGAUCGCGCCACUGCACUCCAGCCUCGGCGACAGAGUGAGACUCCGUCUCAAAAAACCAAAAAACAAAAAACAGUCAAUGGCAUUAAAUAUAAAUACAUUUACAGUGUUGUGUAACCAUCACCACUAUGGAUCCCCCAGACUUUGUCAUCAUCUUCAACCUAAGCGCUCCCUAUUAAAUAGUAACUCCCCACUUUUCCCAGGCCUUGGCAACCACCAUUCUAAUCCCUGUCUCUAUGAAUUUGACUCCUCUCGAUACCUCAGAUAAGCGGCACAAUGCAGUAUUUAUCUGUCAAGUCCGGAAUAUUUCCUUUAGCAUAAUGUCUUCAAGGUCCAUCACGUUGUAGCAUGUAUCUGAAUUUAUUCUUUUAUAAUAUUUUUUAUUUUUUGGAGACAGAAUCUCGCUCUGUCACCCAGGCUGGAGUGCAAUGGCGCGAUCUCGGCUCACCGCAACUUCCGCGUCCCGGGUUCAAGCCAUUCUCCUGUCUCAGCCUCCGGAGUAGCUGGGACUACAGGUGCCUGCCGCCAUGCCCGGCUAUUUUUUUUUUGUAUUUUUUGGGGGUUUUACUGUGUUGCCCAGGCUGGUCUUGAACUGCUGAGCUCAGGCAAUCUGCCUGCCUCAGCCUCCUAAAGUACUAGGAUUACAGGCAUGGGCCACCACGCCCGGCCUUAUUUUUAUUUUUGAGACAGUCUCACUCUGCCGCCCAGGCUGGAGUGCAGUGGUGCGAUCUCGGCUUACCGCAAUCUCUGCCUCCCAGGUUCAAGCGAUUCUCAUGCCUCCGUCUCCCAAGUAGCUGGGAUUACAGGCACCUGCCACCAUGCCCGGCUAAUUUAACGCCCAGCUAAUUUUUGUAUUUUUAGUAGAGAUGGGGUUUCACCAUGUUAACCAGGCUGGUCUCGGACUCCUGACCUCAGGUGAUCCGCCCGCCUCGGCCUCCCAAAGUGCUGGGAUUACAGGCGUGAGCCACUGUGCCUGGCUGAUUUUUAUUCUUUUAGUUAAGGCUGGUUGAUAUUACCUUGUGUGUAUAUACCACAUGUUGUUUAUCCAUUGUUGUUGAUGGACAUGUGGGUGGUUUCACCUUUUGGCUAUUGUGAAUAAAGCUGCUAUGAACACUGUGUACAAAUAUGUUAGAGACCCUGUUUUCAGUUCUUUUAGGUGUGUACCCCGAAGUGGAAUUGCUGGAUUUUAUGGCAAUCCCACGUUUAACUUCUGGAGGAGCUGCUGGAACUGUUUUCCACAGCAGGGGCGCCAUGUUACGUCCCUGCCAGCAAUGCACGCGCAGUUCAAUUUCUCUGCAUACUCACCAAUAUCUGCUGUUUUCCAUUAAAAAAAA